AGUGCGAGGCGCGCGGGGCACGGAGGGCGGUGGCGGCGGGCUCCUGCGAGAAGCAAGCGGAACUUCCUGAGCGUGCUUAGGUGUCACAGCUGGGUGACCCUCCGAAGGAAGGUUUUGCCGCUGGCGCGUCUGGUGUAUCGCGGCCUUGGGGCCGCGGAUCCCUGGGGCUUGCCGCUGCCUCUGGGGUUCGCGCGGCCCUGGCGUCGGGGCUGCCUCAGCGCUGGCUGAAGGCCGGCCCGAAGCACCCUUAAUUGUGGCCGCGCGCUUCCCUGCUGCUCCUGCUGUUCUCCGCGUCGCGGUGGUGGACUCUGGAGGUGGAGCCUUGCCCGGCGAGACGUUGAGGAUUUUGUGAAAAUGGAAAAUUAUGAGGCAUUGGUAGGCUUUGAUCUCUGUAAUACACCGCUCUCCAGUGUUGCUCAGAAGAUUAUGUCUGCUAUGCAUUCAGGUGAUUUAGUGGAUUCUAAGACUUGGGGAAAGAGUACAGAGACUAUGGAAGUGAUAAACAAGUCCAGUGUUAAGUAUUCAGUACAACUUGAAGACAGGAAGACUCAAUCACCAGAAAAAAAGGAUCUUAAAUCUUUAAGAAGUCAGACAUCAAGAGGUUCUGCCAAGCUGUCUCCUCAGUCCUUCAGUGUCAGGCUCACAGAUCAGCUGUCUGCUGACCAAAAACAGAAGAGCAUCAGCUCAUUGACUCUUUCAAGUUGUUUAAUUCCACAGUAUAAUCAAGAGGCUUCAGUUCUACAGAAAAAGGGGCAUAAAAGAAAGCAUUUCCUAAUGGAGAAUAUAAAUAAUGAAAAUAAAGGAAGCAUUAAUCUUAAAAGAAAACAUAUUACAUAUAAUAAUUUGUCAGAGAAAACAAGUAAACAAAUGGCAUUGGAAGAAGAUACUGAUGACGCCGAAGGCUACCUAAAUUCUGGGAACUCAGGAGCAUUGAAAAAACAUUUUUGUGAUAUUAGGCAUUUGGAUGAUUGGGCAAAAAGCCAGCUGAUUGAAAUGCUCAAACAGGCAGCAGCCCUGGUGAUAACUGUGAUGUAUACUGAUGGUUCCACCCAGCUAGGAGCUGACCAGACCCCCGUUUCUUCUGUUAGAGGAAUUGUGGUGUUAGUAAAACGCCAAGCAGAGGGUGGCCAUGGCUGUCCAGAUGCCCCGGCCUGUGGUCCUGUUCUGGAGGGCUUUGUGUCAGAUGAUCCAUGCAUCUACAUUCAAAUAGAGCACUCUGCUAUCUGGGACCAAGAACAGGAGGCACAUCAACAAUUUGCCCGGAACGUGCUAUUUCAAACAAUGAAAUGUAAAUGUCCUGUUAUUUGUUUUAAUGCUAAGGAUUUUGUGAGAAUAGUGCUGCAGUUUUUUGGCAAUGAUGGCAGUUGGAAGCAUGUUGCUGAUUUUAUAGGGCUAGAUCCCAGAAUUGCUGCAUGGCUUAUAGAUCCUAGUGAUGCCACACCCUCUUUUGAAGAUUUAGUAGAAAAAUACUGUGAAAAAUCCAUUACAGUUAAAGUGAACAGCACAUAUGGAAAUUCCUCAAGAAAUAUUGUGAAUCAGAAUGUACGUGAGAACCUGAAGACACUCUACAGACUUACAAUGGACCUUUGCUCUAAACUGAAGGAUUAUGGUUUAUGGCAACUAUUUCGUACUUUGGAGCUUCCUCUGAUACCAAUUUUGGCAGUGAUGGAAAGCCAUGCCAUUCAGGUGAACAAAGAGGAGAUGGAGAAGACGUCAGCACUUCUUGGGGCUCGUCUCAAGGAAUUGGAGCAAGAAGCUCAUUUUGUUGCAGGAGAACGGUUUCUUAUAACGAGCAAUAACCAGCUUCGAGAGAUCCUCUUUGGCAAGUUAAAGCUGCACCUGCUGAGUCAAAGGAACAGUCUCCCCAGAACGGGGUUGCAGAAAUACCCGUCUACAUCAGAAGCAGUGUUAAAUGCUCUGCGAGACCUUCAUCCAUUACCCAAGAUAAUUUUGGAAUACAGGCAGGUUCACAAGAUCAAGUCAACCUUUGUAGAUGGAUUACUAGCUUGCAUGAAAAAGGGCUCCAUUUCCUCUACAUGGAAUCAGACUGGAACUGUGACUGGAAGACUUUCAGCCAAGCAUCCUAAUAUCCAAGGUAUCUCCAAGCACCCAAUUCAGAUUACUACACCUAAGAAUUUUAAAGGUAAAGAAGACAAGAUUCUCACGAUCUCCCCGAGGGCCAUGUUUGUUUCAUCCAAAGGCCACACCUUUCUAGCAGCAGACUUUUCACAGAUUGAAUUGCGCAUUCUUACACAUUUAUCUGGAGAUCCGGAACUUCUGAAGUUAUUCCAGGAAUCUGAAAGAGAUGAUGUAUUUUCUACUCUGACUUCACAGUGGAAGGAUGUGCCCGUGGAACAGGUGACACACGCAGACAGAGAGCAAACCAAGAAGGUGGUGUACGCGGUGGUCUAUGGAGCAGGGAAGGAGCGGCUGGCUGCUUGCCUUGGAGUUCCUAUUCAGGAAGCUGCCCAGUUUUUGGAGAGUUUUUUGCAGAAGUACAAGAAAAUCAAGGACUUCGCCCGAGCAGCUAUUGCCCAGUGUCACCAGACAGGCUGUGUGGUGUCCAUCAUGGGCAGAAGGAGACCCCUGCCAAGGAUUCACGCUCAUGACCAGCAACUCCGGGCACAAGCAGAGCGACAGGCAGUGAACUUCGUGGUGCAAGGCUCCGCUGCUGACCUCUGCAAGCUGGCCAUGAUCCAUGUCUUCACUGCAGUGGCUGCUUCCCACACCUUGACGGCCAGGCUGGUGGCCCAGAUCCAUGAUGAGCUGCUGUUUGAAGUGGAAGAUCCGCAGAUCCCGGAGUGUGCAGCUCUCGUCAGGAGGACCAUGGAGUCCUUGGAACAGGUGCAGGCAUUGGAGCUGCAGCUUCAGGUACCCCUCAAGGUGAGCCUGAGUGCCGGCCGCUCAUGGGGACACCUGGUGCCACUGCAGGAGGCCUGGGGCCCUCCGCCAGGCCCAUGUCGCACUGAGUCUCCCAGCAACAGCCUGGCUGCCCCUGGGUCCCCUGCCAGCACCCAGCCCCCACCCCUGCAUUUUUCGCCUUCAUUUUGUCUGUAGCCCCAGGCAACAGUGGGAGGAGAGAACUGGUUUCCAGCAGUCCAUUGUGUGGCCUUCCCCAAGGUCACCAGCUCUGUACGCCCCAGGACGCAUUAACCCUUUGGGGCUGGGGUGGCCCGCCAUCCCCUGGAGUAAAUGCCUGUGCAAAGCCCUCCUCAUCCUUGUCUGAGUGAAUUCUUCCUGUGAGUGGGAAGUG